GUACGUGGCUUCUCCUUCUGACUGGCUUCAUUCUUUGUGGGUUUAUUCAGCAGGAAUUGUUUAUUCUGAGGGAGUCUUGUAGGUCCUGAGUUAUGAAAAUAUUUCUACAGAACAAUUUGAGUUUGCUUCUUCCCUGGUUCUGGGAACAUUUUUAUAGUGAUCUAUUAGUUCAAGAUACUUACACAGCCUAAACAAUGUAAAUUUGUGCAACACACUUGUGCAUGACAUAGGCUUGGUGUUCUAUUUAGUUUUUUUAAUCGGAUGCAUUUUUUUUCACCCUGAUACUGGAGCACAAUUCAGACUUACUUCCCCCUUCCCUGAGCUACUUGGAGCAGUGGUAGUUCUUCUAGUCCUGUUUUUAUGUAAAUGGAUAUUUUGAAGAAUUCUGACUUGAUGCAGUUAUGUCAGUUCCAGCAUCUUACCUUGCAUGAGCCUUGGGCCAUGUCACCUGUUCUCAAAUGGGCAUCCCAGCCCUAAACCCCUAAGCAGCUGUAUCCAGAUUCAACACCCCUCUGGGUGAUAGCAGUAUUUGCUCUCAUUCUUAUUGGUUUAGCUUUGGAUUCUGGCUUCAUUUCUGGCCUGCAUUAAGAAGAACAGUUAUGUCUUACAGGUAUAUGAGGUACAUUCUUGUGAUGGCUGCCAUGGCUUAUAUUUUGGAACUGAAAGAGGAUCUGGGUAAAUUCAGACUGACAUUUUUAAUGUAAAUUAAUUCACUCACAAACCAUUUAUUGGCCACCUAUCAUGUUCCUGACUUUGUCAUAGGUGCUGGGGCACAACAAUAAAUAACACUGUGUCUUUGCUCCUGUAUAGUUUACAUUCUCAUGGGAAAGACAAAACAAACAAUAAGUAAAACAUAUAGUAAAAUCAGCUGGAGCGAUGAAGAAAAUUAAAGCAGGAGAAUGGGAGAGAGAGGGACUGGUUUGGGUCAUGUGCUUUAUUAGGGUGGCAAAGGAAACCUCUCUGAGGAGUGACCUUUGAGCACAGGCUUACAUGCAGUAAUGAAGAAUCAUGCUGGUAUCUGGGGUGUGAGUCCGUUUUCUCCAAGAAGCAUUACGCCAAGGCAGGAUUGGCUAUGCAAGAGAUUUAUUAAGGCAACUCCUGUGAGCAAGAGUGAGGUCAAGGAAACAAUGAAAAUGUGGGGCUCCUUGUUCAAAAUAACAUUAAGAAUUCCAAGAUGGCUGCAGAGGAGUAUUCAACCAAGCACAGAGCCCUUUUGAAUGCCCUGUCUGACUAUGAGGGAAAGUAGGAGUGAGCUGCUGGGAGCUCGGGAGACUCCUCUGAUUGUGAUGCAGGUCUGACCCCAGGUGAAGAAGACGGGAGGGAGGAGGGUGAGCGGAAGCAUCCUACAGGGCUGUGCUGUUUCAAGAGAGCCUGGAUCUCUUGGAGGAGUCUUUGAGUCCAAGCCACCUCUUAGGUAAGUUUUCAUCUCCCAGGAAUAGGUUUGCAUCACUAUGCCUGCCAUGCUCAGUCACUAUCUAGGAGUAGCCUGUGAGAAAUGUGGCUUCAGCACAAAUGCAGAGAUGGAUUUCAGAGCACAGCAGCUGUAACUCCUAGCCAGUAAUACUCCUUGUAAGUUGGAUGUCUACAAGGCAUAGUCUCAUGGCAGCCACACUGGGUAAAGAGCUUUUCAGGAAGAGGGGACAGUGAUUGCAAAGGCAGUUGUUUUGGGGUUGAAUUAUGUUCCCCAUCCCAAAUUCAUAUGUAGAAUUCCUAACCUGCAAUACCUUUUAACAUGACCUUAUUUGAAAACAGGGUUAUUGCAGAAAAUAAUCAGUUAACAUGAGGUCAUACUGGAGUCGGGUGGGCCUCUAAUCUAAAAUGACUGCUAUCCUCAUAAAAAGGGAAAAUUUGGAGAUAGACAUACACACAGGAAGGAUAACUUGUGAAGAUGAAGGUAGAGAUUGAGGUGCUGAGUCUACAAGCCAAGGAACACUGAAGAUACCAAAAAACCCCACCAGAAACAAAGACGGAAACAUGAAACAGAUUUCUCCCUAGUGCCUUCAGAGAAAGCAUUGCCCAGCCAACACCUUGAUUUCAGAUUUCUUGUCUCCAAAACUGAGACAGUACAUUUCUAUUCUUUAAGCCACCUAGUUUUGAGUACUUUGUUAUGGCAGGCCUAGCAAACUAAUACAGCCUUGAAGUGAUAGAAGACUUGGCAUGUUGUAGAAACAUCAGGGAGGCCACUGUGGAUAGAGCAGAUAAGUAAGGGAGAGAAUCGUAGGGGAAGGAGAGGUAUCCAGGGGCCAGAUCUGUAGAUCAUGACUUUGUAAACCAAUAUAGCAACAUUUGUUUUUAUUCUGAGUGUGAUGGGAAGCCAUUGUAGGGCUUGAAGAGGGCAGUGGCCUGAUUUCACUUAUAUCUUUAAAGUACCACUCUGGCUCCUGUCUGGAAAUAAUAGUUUGCCGAGGAGCAGAAGUGGAGGCAGUGCAACCAGCCCAGUCAAUGGCAGCUGUAAAGAGAGAGAAUCUGGUGGUGUGGACAAGAGUAGUUGUGGUGGAGGGUGUGAGGAGUUUGGGAUGUGUUGGCAAUUUGAAGUAAAUGAUAUACUUUCAAAUUGAUUAGACAGAGCAACUAGACUACUAGAAUUGUUUUCUGAAAUGAGAACACUGGGUGAGGAGCUUAUCUGGAGUUUACAGGAAUGGAUGUCGAUAUCUGCCAUUUUUUAAAAGUCACAUGUUGUUUUGCAAUUUGCUUUUUGAUUUUCAUGAACUUCUUUUCAUAUCAAUACAGAUAUAUUGACCUCCCUGUGUUUUGAGGGCUGCCCAAUAUUUCUUAUGUGGAUAUGCCAUUCUUGAUUAUACUAGUUAUCAAUGAAUGGACUUUUGGUUGUUUCCUUUUGUAUGUGAUUAUAAACAAUGAGGCUUAAACAGCUGUAUGAUUUAUCUAUUGCUUCAUAACAGAAUCCCCUCCAAUGCAGUGGUUUAAAAACAACAACGUUUAUUAUCUCGCAGUUUUUUUGGGUCAGCAGGCAGAGUACAGCGUAGCUGGGUUCUCCGGUUCAGGAUCUCUCCCAAGGCUGAGGCUGCAGCUGUAUCAAGGUUUGACUGGGAAGGAGCCGCCUCGGAGCUUACUCAGUGGUCAUUGGCAGGAUUCAGAUCCUGGUGAACUGUUGGCCUGAGGGCCUUUGCUCCUCACUGGCUGGCUUUUAGCUGGAAGGCACCUUCAGUUCCUUGCUAUGUGGGCCUCUCAGGAGGAGAGCUCACAACAUGGCAGCUGGCAUCAUCAAAGCGAGAGCAAGAGUGUGUGAGCAAGAGAGGUCACAGUGUUUUAUAAGCUAAUCUCAGAAGAGUGCCCCAUCCCUUUUGCUGUAUUCUGUUCACUAGAAGUCAGUCUCUGGGUCCAGCCUUCACUCAAUCAGAGCAUUAUACAAAAGCAUGGAUGCCAGGAGACAGAGAUCACUAGGAGCCACCUUAGAAAUCUGCCUGGCACCAUAACCCAAUACAUUUGUGUUUUGAUAGAUUGUUAAAGGUGGGUUUGCUGAGGGAAAAAGUACGCAUGUUUUAACAUUUCAUAUAUAACAGUGGAUUUCUUUUCAAAAUCUUCAUUCUAGAUUUCAAAGUUUGUUUUGAUGAGACUAUUUGCUACUGCCUGAGAAGGAGAGGCUAUAGCUCCUCAAAGAGCCUUUCCAGAUUUUGUCAUGAAUGUCUCUUCCCUUCUUGCCCUUCUUUUUCUCACCCCUCCAAAACUUCCAGAACAGGAAGUAGCUAUGUGUCUUGCAACAGGAAUGAUACGAAGGUUCUAAUCAGCAGGCACAUGCAUCAUGGUGACUAUUCUAGGGUAUGAUGACCUGGAUUAUGCCAUUAAAAAAUGUCAUUGCCUUCACUUGUGUGCUGACAUGGGUAAGGUUUAUUCAGCCAGCCUUGAUGAGAGGAAUUAAAAAGUAAUCUCUGGUAUAAGGAGUCAGUUUGGGCCCAUGAUGUCUAGGGAAGUUCCACUUGAAUAAUUUCUUCUAAAUCCUCAGAACUCAUGAGCUUCUGGGAGGUCAUACAGUAAUGAGGUAUACAUUUAUUUCCUUAUUAGUCAGAAAGAAACUUUACUUAAAAGGACCCAUUUGUGUUUACUAGAUAUGGUUGGAGGAAAUAUAAAUUAUUAUCACUAUUACUUUAUCUCCUUCCCAUACAAGGCUUUAUAAAAUUAAAUGCAUUGUAAACCUAGACUAUAAUAAAAAUGAGAUCGUGUAAAUAUCUGUGUGUCUUACAGGCUACCUGUAACAAGAUACCUUAGACUGGGUGGCUUAUAAACAACAGAAAAUCUAUUUCUCAUAGUUCUGGAAGCUGGAAAUCCAAUAUCAGGGUACCAGCAUGAUUGGGUUCUGGUGUGGGCCCUCUUGAGGGUAGAAAGCUUUCUGGGGUCCCUUUUAUAAUGGCUAAUCUCAUUCAUUAGGGUAGAGCCCUCAUAACCAAACUAUCUUCCAAAGGUCCCACCUUUUAAUGCCAUCACAUUGGAGGUUAGAAUUUGAACACAUGUAGUCUAUUGCACUGUGGCUGCUAUCAGGUUAGAUGCCCCAUUUGAAAGAUUAGACUGUCUUGGCAGCUUCCCAAAUGAAUGCCAAGGUGCCUUCUUUCCCCUUCUGCUUGUGAGCAAGGUGGGGUGUGUGUGGAACUGGGGAGAGUGCAUGACCUCUGAUGAAGCUGAGGGAAUGUCUUGAUGGGGUCCAUCACCAACAUCCCCUGUUUGGGGCUGACCUCUUGGUUGGAGAAGGUGCUAGAUUCCUUCCCACACUGCCCCUUGCUUUCUAUUGUCAGGUCCCUGUGUUGCCCCAGAGGCCCAUGGCCCUCCUUGAUGUGGAUUAGUUUAGCGACUAGCUCUCAGGGCAACAGGUCCCUCUCUGCUUGUCCAGCUUGGACAGCUUCUCUUUCCUGGGCACCGUGAAGGCCAGGAUCCUGCCUCCUGCCUGUGCCCUCCUGUGAGCCUGGUGCUCUAGGAGCGUGGCUCUCCAAACAGGGAGUGACUCCUCUGUGUCCCAGCACGACCCCACCCUCCCCCUUUGCCUCCCUCAGACACUGGGCAGAUUGUACUCACAUUUCACAAGAUUACUCCGCUAGAUGAGAAAAACGUGUACUUUAUUCAGGACAGCGAGCUCAGCUCUCUGGAUUGCAUUCCUUGCAGAAAUGAGAAUCCAAGUGUAGUGGCCUUUCAAAGCUGAAAUAAAUCAGGGCUCCUUGGCCAUACUACCCUUGUCUGUCAGUUUUUGUCUUUUUCUAGAAGCCAUGCAAGGUUAGGGAAAAUUAAGGGAGAGCAAAUGAGGACCAGUUCAUUGUGUAAUCACUUAAAAUCUCUGAGUUGGAAUAGCUAUCUGUGAUUUAAAACAUAAAUGUUUGCAAAUGGUUUGUAUCUUGAUCAGUUAUGUAAAGACGUGCAUUUGAGAUGCACCAAAGUGACUUUUAGAUGCUUCUUUUUAAAAAUGACAGUCUUAACUUGUGUUUGCGGAACUCUGUAUUUUUCAGUUUUCACCUACGUUAAGCCUUUCAAUUUUUUUGUUGACUAAAGUUGGUAGAAGAAAUGAUUAUCAGAGUUUUUAUGGAAUCCUCCACCACCUUUUUCCAAAAGGAAUUAGAAUCAUCUGGUGCUUAUAUAAAAUCAAACACUGUUUAAACUCAGGGAGCUCUUUUUUUUUUUUUUUUUUUUUUUUUUUAGAAUAAAGUGCAGUUUAAAGAGAAUAGAGUGGGAGCUUUUACCAGAUACCUGUUUUGGUCUCUUGCUGGGCUGAUACUAUUUUCCUAGGAAUGGUGACUGUGUGUUUCUGUUUUUCCUCUUCAGAUUUCUUAGACCAAAUAGAGGAAAUCCACUGGAGGCUUACCUAACAAGACGUAUUGAUGAAUGUAGAAUCUUAAAUGAAAAAGAAGUCAGUGGAUGUGGCUUCCUGUACUGUCAGCUUGGACCAAAAAUAAAGCGAGCCCUCGCCGCAGGGGUUUGGCUCAGCCCUGCGCCUGUGGCAGAUGUUGUUUUCCAUGGCUUUGCUUGAGGAGUACACUUCUCUGGGCAAAAGUUCCUGAGGCCUUUGGAGACUUUUAAAGCCUUUUUUUUUUCUGUAGCUUUUAUUGUUUUUAAGAAAAGUGGUGUCACCCUUACUUGUCAUUAAAAAAAAAAUAGUGUGGGAAAAACAAAUAAACUACCCAAAGAAUAAAACAAGAAAAACCAAAACAACUCCCCUAAAUGAAUGAAAAAAUUUACACCCUUCACUCUUUUGCAAGAUAACUAUUUCCAUGCAAGUUGGAUUAGAAACUAUGAGAAGAUUUUUCUCUUUGAUUUUUGGUUUCUUCUAUUUUUAACAUUUUUGACAAGUCUACACAUUGUGGUUACAUAAAAACAUCAGGAUUAAGAUAUUUGGUAUUUAAAAAGCACCCUUGGACUCGGGAUGAUUCUUUCUGGCCUACAGUGUGCCAGACCCGCUGCUAACCUCUCUUCACCUACUGUCUUAGUUGAUCACCACAAUCCUGCAAGGUAUAACCCACUAAGAGUGUUUUAGGAGAGAGGGAACGUAGCAGCCUGUGGGAUCUGCUUUUCAGGAGUUCCCUAUCCAGAAGGAGGGAGACAUAUGUAUAUGAGUAAGUUCAAGAAAGCAUGAUGUUAGUGAUAAGAAUUAAAGCUAAUGCAUAUUACAAACUUACCUUGCGCUUGCUGCUAUAUCAAAUGCUUUAUUUGGAUAAUGUAAUUUAACUCUCAUGGCAGCCCUUUGAGAUGGAUAUUUUAUCUCCAUUUUACAGAAAUGGAAGAAGAGGAAGCUAACGUUGAGCAAUGUGAUAUAGUAAGCUCCAGAGCCCACACUCUAGAAAUGGUAGAUUUGGGAGUCAAAAUCGGGCAGUCUGAUCUCAGAUCCAUUUACUUAACGACCAGUCUAUACAACACAGUGACCAAGAGCCACAAAGCGCAGGGGUGGUUCAUUGAACUAGCCUCUCCACAGGUGGUGUAGACCAGUAGGGGCAGGGCCAUGUUGUAUAUUCCCAAUAAUGAUUCAGGUUAAUUCUCCUUUCCCCCAAGGACUUUUUCUGCCAUUCUUACUGCUGGAAAUACAACUCUUCAGAUGACCACUUUUGUCUCCUGCCUAUUCGCCUCAGGAAAUGACUUUUGGCCCAUGGACCACUGGAUAUGCCAGGCCAGGCAUGUCAGACUCCCUGGCUCAGGGAGCUCUUAAAUCCUGGAGAGCAGCAGAGUCCACACAUCCACUGGAAAGAACAUGAGGUUCCCUUGGAAAUCAUUCAAGAGGAAGAUGGAAGGGGCUGUUUAGAAGAGCUUAAAAGCUACAGGCUGUAAGACUGGGGCCUGAGUGCUGGCAGUGGAAAACACUGUUGGGCUGUGAUCUCUCCCUGAAAAGUUCCAGGUGCCUUUUCGCUUCCUGCAAAAGAAAGGAAGCGAAAGAGAAGACCAUGUCCAUAGCCCUGAAGCAGGUAUUCAACAAGGACAAGACCUUCCGACCCAAGAGGAAAUUUGAACCUGGCACACAGAGGUUUGAGCUGCACAAACGGGCUCAGGCAUCCCUCAACUCGGGUGUGGACCUGAAGGCGGCUGUGCAGUUGCCCAGUGGGGAGGACCAGAAUGACUGGGUGGCAGUACAUGUGGUGGACUUCUUCAAUCGGAUCAACCUCAUCUAUGGCACCAUCUGUGAGUUCUGCACCGAGCGGACCUGUCCUGUGAUGUCAGGGGGCCCCAAAUAUGAGUAUCGGUGGCAGGAUGAUCUCAAGUAUAAGAAGCCAACAGCGCUGCCAGCUCCCCAGUACAUGAACCUUCUUAUGGAUUGGAUUGAGGUUCAGAUCAACAACGAGGAAAUAUUUCCAACAUGCGUGGGUGUUCCCUUCCCAAAGAACUUCCUUCAGAUCUGCAAGAAGAUCCUGUGCCGCCUUUUCCGGGUCUUUGUCCACGUCUAUAUCCACCACUUCGACCGGGUCAUUGUGAUGGGUGCAGAGGCCCAUGUCAACACCUGCUACAAACACUUCUAUUACUUUGUCACAGAGAUGAACCUCAUAGACCGCAAGGAGCUAGAGCCUUUGAAAGAAAUGACGAGCAGGAUGUGUCACUAAUGCUCCACCUCACCCUUUGGAAGAAAGGAAAGCUGUUUCCUCCUGGUGCCCUGAGCGGGCAGGAGGUGGACCACCCUGGCUGAAAUGACACACCUACUCCCAGGAACAGCAGAGGUGGAGGCAAGCAGUGACUCCUGAGAGACAUUCCCCACUCACUUUGUGUGCUCUUAACCUUCUGAGUGCUGCUAGCCCAGACCUGUGGACGAGGCAGACCACAACGUGAAAGAAGGACCAGCCCCUUGACCGUUCUGGCUGGGGAAUUGUCCACGAGGAAGCCUCUGCACUUCCACACAUGGCACAGUUCUGCCUGUGACCUGCCGCCUAAGCUUUACUGGAAUUCAGGUUUUGAGACUGAGAUGCGUGUUCGUAUUUUUCCACUUAUCUGUCUUGUCAGCUGGCCGACUUCUCUGUGAUUGGUUUUUUAAGUGCCGGGUGAAUUUUGGACCUCUGGAUGUGCAGCAAGUUUUUAUGCAAUAAGCCUUCCUUUCAGGUCUCUAAAAGCUCCUGCUCUGAUCUGUGGUUUAACACUGUGCAGGGCUGUGGAGCUCUGAGACACCUGAACCCCUACCCAUCCCCUGCACCUCCCUACUCUCCCUGCCGAGGCGUCCAUAGCAUUUCCCUAAUAAAUAGUUUUAUCAGGGACACUCCAUGGGGUGGCUUGUCUCUGCCCCAAACAGGGUCUUCACGUUCUAACUGCAGGGAAGAGACUGGUUACUAGCGUAAAGCUGACAAGUUACCAGUUCACCUGAUCAGAAUGUAUUUUUUAUAACCACCAUCAUUCCUUGUCUCUUCAGUGGAAGAUAUUCUUUCCUGUUUCCCAGAAGAGAGAAAUAAAAGUCCUAAAUAACUAAGAAUGAUCAGCGGGAGCGUUGGGCAUGAUUACUGCAGUGUUUGUUCUUUAUUAAAGACAGGGAGUCGUGGCUGUCUCUACAUAAUACUAACAUUUCAGUGAAAAAAGUACAAUUGGUUAUUUGGUACGUGUAGAUUUAACACCCAGACGGCUGACUUGUAACCCUCCCCACUAGCCUUCUGAGCAUUUAAACCCAGCCGUCAUUCUCUCCCCACUCCACGCUCCCCACUCCUCUGCCACGUUAUGUUACGGCACAAAAUUAAUUUCUGCCCCUGUGAUUGGGCCACGGUUGCCAAGGUAACAGUGGAGCUGGAGCUAACUUCCUUCUUUCAUCCUUUCCAAUUUUUCUAUUCCAGAAGACAGUCAGAAUAAUGCAUUCUGUACUACAUCCUGCCUUUUGAAACCUAAAUGAGUUUUCGUUGAUGAAAUGUUGCCUUCUCUGAUUCAUUCACAAAACUGUGGUGGUUCUGACCACCUGUGACGAGGGGGGUCAUAAUACUUCCAGUGAUCCUUUUAAUUUAGCAAAAUAUUUGUCGGUGGAGGGAAGUAGAUAAGAAUGUAUUAGUGUAUUUUAAAGUAAUAAUGAUUAAAGAAUAACUAAAUGACUCUGAUUUUGUUUUAUCAAUCAUAAUGUGUUAAAGCCCUCUGUGGCUGCCACAAAAGACUAGAAUCAUGAAAUCUUUGUCCAAGCUAAGAAAGGGCUGUCUCUGUGGGUACAGUGGCAUUCUCUGUUGACCUAACCAAGCAGCCUGAACCUUGCUUUGUGUCUCGUAAAGGUCAUCUCACGGAAUCCAAUUGCUGCUACCUCACCAUGUUGCUGUGCCCUGGUCAACAAUAAACAUACUUUUGUCCCCCUUCCUAAGUAACUUUGAGAGGACAAGAUAGGCAAAGUUUUUUCCCUACAUCUCUUUUGGCCAAAAGAAUAUCUGACCAUCACAGAGAUCCAGAGAACAGAAACAAGAGCCCCUAAGUCCCAGCCUCUGCAAUACACAGUUACCAGAUGGGAAUGCAGCACAGUGGCACAGAGAGGUAACUACGGAGCCCAUGCCCUGGAGGAACUCUGUAGCUGUGCAUCAUGGAACGCCACAGGAUUUUUACAUUAAAAAGUUGAAUAUGUUCCUGCAUUUCAGCAGUGCAUAAUCGAGCAGGAGGCUGGAAUCUGGAGACCUUUGUUAUUCAUUCUUUUUAAGGUUAUUUUUUAUUAACUGUGCAUAUGAAAUUUCCACUCAAUUUAAAAAUCCAAAUCUUUUUAAGCUUCUUGGAAGAAUUUCCUCCUGCUUAUAUUGUUAAUUGCACUAAUGAACUCUUCUAGGGUAAAUUCUGGCAAACUACCCUUUUUUUUUUUUUAAUCACAGAAUAUUCCUGUUCCCACAGAACUUUGGCACAUUCUGAAGAAAAUCUCUGCAGUCAAUUUUUAUCUCCUCUGCUUGACUGCAUCUAACUGUUCAUCUCUGUUAUAAAUGGAGCUUCAGCCCUCUGGGUCAGAGACUGACAACCCUCCUUCUUCUUCCUAACCUGUCCUACUCUCCUUCUUUUUCUGCUUUCAUUUUAAUUUUGGGAAAUUUUAAAGUAAAAGUUUCAAAGUUGAAAGAUUAUAGUGAGUACCCUUAUGUCCUUUAGUGCAUCAGUUGUUAAUGUUUUGCCUUGUUUUCUUUUCUUCCUUUUUUUUUUUUAAGAGAAGGGGUCUCUCCCUAUUUUACCCAAGCUGGCCUUGAACCCCUUGCCUCAAGUGAGCUUCAACCUUAGCCUCCUGAGUAGCCAGGACUAUGGCAUGUACCACCGCACCUGCCUCACAUUUUCUUUCUCACUGUAAAUACACAUUCUUAUUCUUGAACCUUCUGAAAAUAAGUUGCAGACAUCAUGAAAAUGUAAAAUACUUCAUCAUAUUCUUUCUUUUAAUAAGAGCAUUGUCCUAUAAAUCUGCAAUAUUUUCACGCCCAUGAAACUGAACACUGAUACUGCAUAAAUCUAAUAUAUGAUCCAUAUUCAAAAUUCUCCAGUUGUCCCCAAAAUAUCCUUUAUAGCUGUUUAUUUUUAAAUCCAGGAUCCAAUCAAGAAUUAUACGUUAUAUGUAGUUGUCAUUCUCUUUUGUUUCCUUUAAUUGAUUAGAGUUGCCCUUUUGUGUGUGUCUGAGUGGUGGGUGGUGGGGUGGUGUUUGUGUAUGAUGUGCAGUGUGUGUGUGUGUGGUGUGUCUUUCAUGACACUGACAUUAUUAAAGAGUUCAGGCAAGUUUGUGGAAUGUCCCACAAUCUAGACUUUUUUACUGAUUGUUUCCUCAUUACGAGAUACAGGUUACAUUUUUUUUCCCAAGACUGCUACAUGUGUGAUGUUGUUUCCUUACUACUGCCUCACCUCAGGAAGCACAUAAUGUCUACUUGUCUCUUUUCUGAUAUUAGGACUGAUCAGGUGUUGUCUGCCUGAUCCAAUCAUUAUCAAGUUCCAUAAUUCAUUAUUAAGCUCUGAAAUUCAGGACACAUACAUUUAUAGAGUGUGAGGCUGUGCAUACGUACAUUCAUCCCUUAAUGUUCUCAAGGAGGCCCAGGAUCCCCAAAAUAUUAUAAGCAUUGCAGUCAGAUGAUAUAGCACUAGCAAAGCAUUCAUCCCUUUCCAUAUAACAGGAGGGAGGGGAAGAAGGAAGUUUCCAUGUGCAGGCAAUACGUGAGAGCAUGGGCAAGUGAGGAUUUGUAUGCUCCCUGUAGCCAGAGGUGAAAUAUUCAACGCUUUUAUUUUUUCUCCCGUCUUCAAUGACCUCCCAUUUGGACCCAUAGUUUAUUUAUAGAGAGCACACACUCCCUAAUUGUCAGAUGGUUUUUUUGGGAAAACUCUUAGAUAGUACAGUGAGUUGUGACCCUCCAAAGGAUCACAAGUACAUAAACAGAUACAAAGUAUUUAUGUGGUAUUAAAAUUUCAUGGUGAUGGUGCAAGGGAGAGAUGAUUAGGAAGAAAAUGUCUUACACGGCUGUAAUUGAGAAAUACUGAUCUAGAGUCAUUUCCUGCUUCUUAAAUUGUUCGUUUUCUCUUCCCUGGGUAUUUUCUCAUUUCCAAAGACCCAGAGUCUCAGAGCCAGGUUAAGUGGAAGAAACUUUGAGAGGUUUCUUAAUCAAUUCCUUCUAUCUCUCAAACCAUGCCAGUAACUUCCUUGGUGAAAAAAUCUAUACUCCUCUCACAGUUCUUCGGGCAUGGAAAUUCUAUAGCAUUCUUUGGUAUAACCAACCCACUGAACCCUCCACAACAUCUUGAAUUCCAUUCAACUCGAGCUGAAGUAUUCUUUUUGAGUUUCAGUAUAUCUUUUCUAGUGUCCCACUUUUAGAAAGGUCCAAAGAUGAUAUAUAAUAAGUGAAAAUACAAUUAAUCAGAGCUUUAUUUGCAUAUCCAUUAAAUAUCUGAAGGCUAUUACCAGUUGUGCUUCAGCCUCCUUUCCCUUGCAAUUCUCCCAGGGUGGCAUCCUCUACGGAGUCUUGUUGCUCCAUUGUUGACCACUGAUGUAACUCAACGUGAAACCUUCCCAAAGCUCUCCACAUCACUCUCUGUUAUGGCUGUGACCAGCAGUGAACAUGAAAAGAACUUAUUUCAUGCCUUCUCCAAACUAUAUUGUUUCUUUGCUAAGUCCAGACCUGCUUUUUCUACAUUUAUAGGUUUUCUAUUUUAAUCGCCAUGCAAAAUUCUUUAUCAUACUCAAUCAUUUUGGUUUAUCUUCCUGACUUCUUACCUUUAACAUCCCUGUUAAAGAUUACACUGUUGUUGUUUCAAAAAAAAAAAAAAAAAAACCUUAAUUGGCAAAACAUUAAGGGACUUGAAUAGAAUUACACUUAUCUUUUUGUGCUGAUUUAUGUCAAUCCAUCAUUCUGGUUAUUGAUGGAAGCAAAUUGCUUCCUAUGUUCUCUAAACCUUAUGUCCCUUCCAUACUCCAUGAGUACCACACUGGGAGAAAACAAAAGCAAAAAGAUUGUGGGAAAAGUAUAGCCAUUAUCUUUGAGGAAAUGUGUACCAAGGCACAAUCAUUAAAAGGAGUUGGAGGCAUCAUUUGGUUGACACUGUUGUCAUUCUUGUUCUGAUCAUUUUGGACCUUGAAGAAAUUGGUGAUUCUCUCCUAGAAUUAGACAAACAAAGUGUGUUUGGAAAUAAUGAUUGUUUUCCUGCCUUAAAAAAUAUAUUAACAGAAAGCUUUUAUAACAGGCUGUUUCCCUCUGGACAGGUAUUAAUUCUGAGUAAGAAUUUUCAGUGACUACAUAAGGAUUUGUGUAACUUAUGAAGGAAGAGUCCAUUUCUAAUCAAAUAAUUCGCCUGUUUUACUAGCUUAUAGUGAUCUGAUUUCAGAAUUUUCCUGUAUCUUUUUUACAUACAUCAGAAAAAGAAAUGUUUACUAUAUUUUUGGUUCCAUUUAUGAUUGUAUUAAGCAUUUGACUAUAAGGAAAACUAACAAUUAAAUCAAUUAGAAAAGCAACAUAAAAUUAAAUGAUAUUUAGGAAAUCAGUUAUAUGUGAGCUUGGGUAUUCAAAUGUCACAAAUAAAAAGCAUAUAACCAUUA